GUGGAGAAGGGCUGCGGGAAGCAGAACACCGCCCCCAGCGCCCAGCGUGCUCCAGAAACAUGAGCACAAACGCCUCAGCCUCCUUCCCCGGCGGCACCGGCACCGGCACCAGUACCCGCACCAGUACCGGCACCGGCACCAGUACCCGCACCAGUACCGGCACCGGCACCAGUACCCGCACCAGUACCGGCACCGGCACCGAGCGCAAGGCGGAGGGCCCGCCCGAAGCCGGGGGCACAACUGCCCAGGUCCCGAACCCGGACUCCAGCUUGGACGACACCUCCUACAGCCUGUCCGAAUGGAGCGUCCGUUCUGAGUGGCGGUCCGUCUCGGAUCCGCUAGCCAGUUCCCAGUGGAGCACGUCCUCAACUGCCGAGGCCGCCUCCUGGAGCUCCAGCAUACACUCCCCAAUCAGCACUACCGGUCUUAGCGAGAGUACUGACUCCGACUCCAAGAGUGGCCUCCGGGGUUUCAGCGCUUACAACCCGAGCAGUCGGAUCCCCAAGUCUACCACCAGCUCGAACUCCUCCGAUGGGGCCGUCACAGCCUCCAAUCAGGACACCGGCAUUCCCUGGGUAUUAGUAACAGGACCUACCCCGCCCGUAAACUCCCCCGUAGAGUCAUUGCAAGGGUCUGCCUUCUCCUCAGGGUUCAGCACCCCACGGGGUUUGGUAAAAGGACCGACCCUGCCCCCGGAUUCCAACCUGACCUCAGUGUCCGACUACACUUGGAUAUUUGUACGGGGACCUCCUAUACCCAAUGACCUUUCGCAAGUGUCAAUACAAGCACCUCCUACACCCAGUAACACCCCCGAGUGUCAGUACAAGGGUCUGCCGCAUCCUCAGUGUCCAGCUUCCCCUGGGGUUUGGUACCAGGACCACCUCUACCCAAUAACAUUUCCCCAGUGUCGCCACAAGCACCUCCUGCACCCCAUAACAUCCCCCCAGUGUCAAGGCAGGCGUCUACCCCCACCUCAGUGCCUGACACUCCGCGGGGUUCAAUACAAGAACCUCCUGCACCCAGUAAUCCUUUCCAGCUGCCGACACAAGGACAUUCUAAACCUAAUAACUCUCGCCGAGUGUCAGUACAAGGGUCCGCCCCGCUCUCAGUGCCCAGCUCCCCCCGGGUAUCAGCUGAAACAUCAGCUCCGCCCCUGGGCGCUCCCGGAGUAUCAGCAAAAGGGUUCGCCCCGCCCACAGUGCCCGGCUCCCCCCGGGUAUCAAAAGAAGGAUCGGCUCCGCCCCCGGGCUCCCCGGGGGAGUUGAUAGAAGGGUCCUUCCCACCCUUUGCCGUCCCCACUCCUGUGCCUACGACCCAGGAGCGUGUCAGCCAAAGCAUGGAGAAUCAAGAGAAGGCGAGUAUCGCGGGCCACAUGUUCGACGUAGUCGUGAUCGGAGGUGGCAUUUCAGGCCAAGAGAAGAGAUUGGCAUGAACUGUUGCUUUGCCAGUUCCAGCCAGUACCAGCAAAAACAUACAUGUAUGUUGGAGCAUCAGAGGAAAGCAGCUCCUGGUGGAGAGACUAUCUGCUGCCAAACUCUUGACUGAAUAUGGCGUUAGUGUUUUGGUUUUAGAAGCUCGGGACAGGGUUGGAGGAAGAACAUAUACUAUAAGGAAUGAGCAUGUUGAUUACGUAGAUGUUGGUGGAGCUUAUGUGGGACCAACCCAAAACAGAAUCUUACGCUUGUCUAAGGAGCUGGGCAUAGAGACUUACAAAGUGAAUGUCAGUGAGCGUCUCGUUCAAUAUGUCAAGGGGAAAACAUAUCCAUUUCGGGGCGCCUUUCCACCAGUAUGGAAUCCCAUUGCAUAUUUGGAUUACAAUAAUCUGUGGAGGACAAUAGAUAACAUGGGGAAGGAGAUUCCAACUGAUGCACCCUGGGAGGCUCAACAUGCUGACAAAUGGGACAAAAUGACCAUGAAAGAGCUCAUUGACAAAAUCUGCUGGACAAAGACUGCUAGGCGGUUUGCUUAUCUUUUUGUGAAUAUCAAUGUGACCUCUGAGCCUCACGAAGUGUCUGCCCUGUGGUUCUUGUGGUAUGUGAAGCAGUGCGGGGGCACCACUCGGAUAUUCUCUGUCACCAAUGGUGGCCAGGAACGGAAGUUUGUAGGUGGAUCUGGUCAAGUGAGCGAACGGAUAAUGGACCUCCUCGGAGACCAAGUGAAGCUGAACCAUCCUGUCACUCACGUUGACCAGUCAAGUGACAACAUCAUCAUAGAGACGCUGAACCAUGAACAUUAUGAGUGCAAAUACGUAAUUAAUGCGAUCCCUCCGACCUUGACUGCCAAGAUUCACUUCAGACCAGAGCUUCCAGCAGAGAGAAACCAGUUAAUUCAGCGGCUUCCAAUGGGAGCUGUCAUUAAGUGCAUGAUGUAUUACAAGGAGGCCUUCUGGAAGAAGAAGGAUUACUGUGGCUGCAUGAUCAUUGAAGAUGAAGAUGCUCCAAUUUCAAUAACCUUGGAUGACACCAAGCCAGAUGGGUCACUGCCUGCCAUCAUGGGCUUCAUUCUUGCCCGGAAAGCUGAUCGACUUGCUAAGCUACAUAAGGAAAUAAGGAAGAAGAAAAUCUGUGAGCUCUAUGCCAAAGUGCUGGGAUCCCAAGAAGCUUUACAUCCAGUGCAUUAUGAAGAGAAGAACUGGUGUGAGGAGCAGUACUCUGGGGGCUGCUACACGGCCUACUUCCCUCCUGGGAUCAUGACUCAAUAUGGAAGGGUGAUUCGUCAACCCGUGGGCAGGAUUUUCUUUGCGGGCACAGAGACUGCCACAAAGUGGAGCGGCUACAUGGAAGGGGCAGUUGAGGCUGGAGAACGAGCAGCUAGGGAGGUCUUAAAUGGUCUCGGGAAGGUGACCGAGAAAGAUAUCUGGGUACAAGAACCUGAAUCAAAGGACGUUCCAGCGGUAGAAAUCACCCACACCUUCUGGGAAAGGAACCUGCCCUCUGUUUCUGGCCUGCUGAAGAUCAUUGGAUUUUCCACAUCAGUAACUGCCCUGGGGUUUGUGCUGUACAAAUACAAGCUCCUGCCACGGUCUUGAAGUUCUGUUCUUAUGCUCUCUGCUCACUGGUUUUCAAUACCACCAAGAGGAAAAUAUUGACAAGUUUAAAGGCUGUGUCAUUGGGCCAUGUUUAAGUGUACUGGAUUUAACUACCUUUGGCUUAAUUCCAAUCAUUGUUAAAGUAAAAACAAUUCAAAGAAUCACCUAAUUAAUUUCAGUAAGAUCAAGCUCCAUCUUAUUUGUCAGUGUAGAUCAACUCAUGUUAAUUGAUAGAAUAAAGCCUUGUGAUCACUUUCUGAAAUUCACAAAGUUAAACGUGAUGUGCUCAUCAGAAACAAUUUCUGUGUCCUGUUUUUAUUCCCUUCAAUGCAAAAUACAUGAUGAUUUCAGAAACAAAGCAUUUGACUUUCUGUCUGUGGAGGUGGAGUAGGUGAAGGCCCAGCCUGUAACUGUCCUUUUUCUUCCCUUAGGCAAUGGUGAACUGUCAUUACAGAGCCUAGAGGCUCACAGCCUCCUGGAGGAAGCAGCCUCCACUUUGGAUCAGGAAAUAGUAAAGGAAAGCAGUGUUGGGGGUAGCGGCAUGCAGACCCUCAGACCAGAAUGGGGACAUCUUGUGGUCUGCUGCCUCAGGAAUCUCCUGACCACUUGUAGUCCCUCCGACUUCUCUAGACAUCUAGUCUCAGUGCUAGCUUAUUUGUAUUUUUCCUCUUUCACUUCUUAUGGAGGAGAGUGUUUAACUGAGUUAGAAUGUUGAAACUGACUUGCUGUGACUUAUGUGCAGCUUUCCAGUUGAGCAGAGGAAAAUAGUGGCAGGACUGUCCCCCAGGAGGACUCCCUGCUUAGCUCUGUGGGAGACCAACUACGACUGGCAUCUUCUCUUCCCCCUGGAAGGCAGCUAGACACCAAUGGAUCCUUGUCAGUUGUAACAUUCUAUUUCAACUUCAGGAAAGCAGCAGUUUUCUUUUAAUUUUUCCUAUGACCAUAAAAUUAGACAUACCUCUCAACUUACAUAUGUCUUCAACAUGGUUACCUCUGCAUAAAUAUUAGCAAAGCAUGCCAAUUUCUCUUAAGUACUGAAAUACAUAUGAUAAAUUUGACUGUUAUUUGUUGAGACUAUCAAACAGAAAAGAAAUUAGGGCUCUAAUUUCCUUAAAGCAAGCUCACUUGCUUUAGUUGUUAAGUUUUAUAAAAGACAUGAAAUUGAGUCAUUUUAUAUAUGAAAACUAAGUUCUCUAUCUUAGGAGUAAUGUCGGCCCACAAGGGUGCCCACCUCUUGUUUUCCCCUUUUAAAAACUCAGAUUUUUAAAAGCCCUUUCCAAAGGUUUCAACUGUAAAAUACUUCUUUUUACAAUGUAUCAACAUAUUUUUAUUUAAGGGGAAUUAACAAUUGCCAGGGAAACCAGCCAACCCAAGUUUAUUAUAUCAUUAACCUUAUCAUAAAUUCAAACCUAAGUUGCUGGACCCUGGUGUGAGGACAUAAAUCUUCCAAAGUUUUGCCUAUCCUAAGAGCUGCAUUUUUCUACUGCUCUUUACCUUGCAUUUUAGCUAAUUUAGGAGUUUUGAGAAUGUAUUGGAUACGCUCCAGUACAUAAGGAGUUGCCGCAUAUUAUAUCAGACUGCUUUGAGAAAUCUCAUCCCUAGUCUAUUGCAGUUGUUUCUAUUAGCUUACUGAUUAACUCAGUCCUGACACACCUUUUGGGAAAUGCUGAUUUAAACUUCUUAACUGGCAACAGUUGGAACAGUAAUCAGUUUGCUAACAUAUUUAAAGUCUUGAAUGUUGAAGAACUCAUGUGAUUUACCCUUUUCAACUUUUUGGAAAACGAUUUAAUUUAUUCUAAUUAGAUUAACCCUAUUAAUCUAUGGAUUGGGUAUCAAAAUGAAUGCCAGUCCAGAUGUGCCUAGACACGAAAUUGGAGCUGAGGACUCUCACGAUAUGCAAGUUCAUCCAACGUGAAGAUACCAUAAGCUUUUUCUCUGAACCAGAGAAAUGAAAGUCAGUUUAAGAGGCUGAUAGAUCUUGGCCCUGUUAAGGCAUCCACUUCACAGUUCUGAAGGCUGAGUCAGCCCCACUCCACAGUUAGGCCAAGAAUUAGAUUUUAAAACUUCAUCUGUCUGUCCCAGUUAACUGUUAAAUAAGGCCUCAUCCUCCACUGAAGAGUAUGGAUUGAAGGAUUGUGAACUAUGUUUAGUGUGAUUGUGAACUUGGUGCCUAAUGUUCCAUGUCUGAAGUUUGCCCCAGUGCUACACGUUGGAGUAUACCUAUGUGUGUGCUUUGCCACUGAAGUAAGAUUUUGCCUGUAUGGUACUGUUUUGUUUGUUAAUAAAGUGCACUGCCACCCCCAA